GGAGCUAGCGCUCAAGCAGAGCCCAGCGCGGUGCUAUCGGACAGAGCCUGGCGAGCGCAAGCGGCGCGGGGAGCCAGCGGGGCUGAGCGCGGCCAGGGUCUGAACCCAGAUUUCCCAGACUAGCUACCACUCCGCUUGCCCACGCCCCGGGAGCUCGCGGCGCCUGGCGGUCAGCGACCAGACGUCCGGGGCCGCUGCGCUCCUGGCCCGCGAGGCGUGACACUGUCUCGGCUACAGACCCAGAGGUAAGAGGGCCUGGCUGGGGGCGUCAGGGAUGAGCUGACGGCCCAUGCCACGGAAGAGAGGUAAGAAGUGGGGGCCCGCGCCUCCACCCGGCACAGGGUAAACGUUACCCGCCUCAGUUUCUGUUUGUCUGUCCACCCUGUGCUGUGCAGUCUACCUCUAUCUGUCUGUUUGUCCAUGCGUCUGUUGAUGGGCACACGCUCUUGGCACUGUCCUCUGUGGGAUUUCUCUGAGAUCUUGUGAUGCUUUACAAGCUGCAGGUGCCGGGGGGCGCUGGAGUCCCCAGAGGGCAUCCAGAGGGGGCAGACUCCUGCUUUCCGUAGAUUUUCCCCCUUCUGAAUGGCACCGGGGGCUUGCGCCCGGGAGAGUGUCUCGCCGAGGAGGGAGUACCACAAGGGUCAGGUCUCGGUGUCCUGCCGACUGGGAGCCAGCUCACGCCGAGCUCUAGCGGGCGUGCGCCUAGCAACAGGUCUGCGCCCUGCUGCUCCUGCCUCAGCACGCUCUUCCUCCCAGUUUCCCUCGCCUCCCAGUGCCUCCGGGACAGCGCUAGGCACCCAGCGACGCGCUGGCGCGGGGCCGAGCUGAGGCAAUUGCAAUGUUAGAUGAACCCGGGGGGCUCUGCUGAUGUUUAGACUGAGACUCCAAACGUGGCAUCGCUGGAAGAAGGUCUGGUGGUCCCUGGCAAAGGACGUCGGCUCCAAGAAAGGUCGCGUUAGGUUGUGAGGAAAGGCAGAGAGUCCUGGCAGAACGCUGGCCAGGUCUCCAGCUCGCCGCUCUGGGAACGAAGGCCAGUGACAUUCUGGAAUGGACCCCAAGGGAUGCGUGUGCUCAUGAGAGAGGAGCGCUGUGCGCCCUGGGUCCUCAGCCGCAGACACUCUCUGCGACAGCCGCUGUUCCCCAAGGGUCGGACGCUACGGCAGUCCCAGGAGUUCCGCCAGCUGCCGGGUUUGAGGUCCUGAGUCCUUCUCCAAGCAGCCAACGCUACCCACAGGUGAGAGCUCCCUUUAAAAACUAAUCUUCUGAUGUGUGAGCCAGUGCCUGGCUGCAGCCCCAUACCAGGGACGGUGAGCCGGGGAGCGCGUCUCUCCAUCCCUGCGGUCUGGAAAGUGAUCCAGGGCGCGCCCGAGGGCGGGGAGCCGGCGGCUCUGCGUGCCCAGGCGCGACGCCACCAUGGACAGCUCCCAGCCACUUCCUCCACUCGGGGUCUGUGGCCCUGGGUCUCCGGGGAAGUCGUGCGCUUUCUUCCCAGACCCAAGGCGUUGGGGCGCUGGGAAAGAGGAAAGGGACUGAGAGUCCGCUGGGGCCCUCGGUAUUACCACUCAGGAGGCAGCCCAGCCCUCAGGAGUCUGUGGUUUGUGACCAGGUCCUAGCUGAGCCGGCAGUUCUGCAGGACCUCCCGGGGGCACUCUGUGGUUCUCUGGCUUUUCUAUGACACCACGGAGACCCCUCAGAGCUGUUAGGAAAGUAUGGCCCCUGAGAAUCCGACCCAGGCAGUGAGAUAAUGCCAGAUACAAUUACGCCAGACAUAAUUAGGGAUCCAGCUCAAACUGUUUUCUGUGUAGGGCACAAGUUCAUGUGUUCCAUCAAAUUAAAUUAUUUAUUUAGUACAUAUGGGAUUGGGAGGAUAUAUUAGUUUUACGAUUAAUGAUAGAAUGGAGAAGAAAUCAAAUAGAGCAAAUUUAUAGAGAAGGCAAUCGGAUGCAUUUGCAAAAGCAACUAUGCGGUUUUCUGAUCCUAAUAGUUUUGUUCAAAGCCCAUGACUUUCUUAAAGCAAUUUCCAAAGGCUCCUUUUUAGCCCAGUAGAUGACUUUUCAAGUUGGUCACUUGAAACAGGGUGGAAAAACCUGUAGGGUUUAAUCUGUGCACCAAAUUAAAGAUCUCCCUUCUCUGGUAAGAAACGACACUGGAUGGGGCUCUUUUUGUCAUUUCCACCCAUACUGAAGUGUGUAUCUUCCUUUAUUUUAAAAUUACAAGAAACGCAGGUCUGCUUUUUUUGUGUGUGACUGACAAAGGCCGACGGAGAGUAAAAACAAGUAAACACCUCUUAUAAAAAAAAAUUUUGAGACAGCAUCUGUGACUUUGGGAAAGUUGCUCAAAUGUUUUGUGCCUGUUUGCUGAUAUGUAAACUGGGAAUAACGCAAUGCCAUCUUGCAGGGUUGCUAUGAGAAUUACAGUAAUUGGUACAAUGUAAAGCAUUUAAUCCAGUGCUGAGCAUAGAGAAAUCGUUUUAAAUGGUAGCAAUUACAGGUAUAUUUUAAAGACAGUUGUGCAUUUCUUUUGAAUUAUGUUCACCAUCCCUUUGCCCUCUCUCUUAACCUAGUAACUGUUUGAUAGGGACUCCAUCUUCACUUUAUUUUUGCAUCCGAGAACUUGUUGAUGGAAUUGAUGAAAAUGCUGGAGUUGAUCACAAUGAAAAAAAAAUUCUUAUUUAAAGACAAAUGGAAGAACUUUUAUGUGAUAAAAAUCGGUCAACUGUUUUCCCCUACCUACACUACUUGGAGGAAAGAUAAAACUCAGAAGGAAUCUUAGCUUCUUCCGUCUAAAAGGAUUGGAGCUGAAGAAUACAUGCUACAGAUGCUCAGAAUCUUUCUAUGAGACUGCUGGUGACAUGAACAGAGCAGGAGGACAUGGGGCCUUGGAUGACCUUGAAUUCCUGGCUGUCUUCUGUGGACUCCCAUGCAGAUUCCAGUUUCCAGCAUACCCAUGGCUUUCUGAUGGAGAAGGUCAGUGAAGCCGCAUCACUUAUGCAGCUCCAGGUGGGGGUCACUCGGCUCAAGGUGGUGGAGUUGGAACUCAGACCUAUGUCACCGUGACAAGCCCUGGACUCCGGUGCGGCUGGGCCUGGGGCUACCUGAAGGGAGAGCAGAGACUCAGGUGCCCGGUGAGCAAUGGCAGUGAGGAGAAGCAGAGAGCAACGCCAGCAAGCAACGCCUCCUGCCCCUGCUUUUGCUCUUGUGUCUCUUGACCCUGUGAGGUCCAGCAACCAUGGGGACUGAGCAGCAGUUGGACUUGGGGGCAGCCGAGCUUCUGGAAAAUUUUAGCUUGUUAUUGUGAAGACUUGUGGAAUAUCCCAAAGUGCUGGCUUUCGGAAAAGGGUGCCUACAUUUUCUUCUGCACAGGCUCUGCUGAAGGAGUUUGCUGCACUCUUGAAAGGACAGGCAAGCUCAGGUCCUCAUGGCUCGAUCUCUGAGCAGGCCUCUAACCCAGUGAGGACAGCGGUCAACCAGUCUCCAGCUAACAGCUUCCUGCAGAGACUUCCAGCAUUGUUAGCUAACAUGCACUCUUCUGAGGCCUUCAACAGCUGGAAACUGUUUCAGGACUAUCUUGCCAGCUAAGAAGCGGAAUCCCAGUUCUUGUUGCCAGGAAGCUUUUAAUGGCCAAUGGAGAAUGCUGUCCUCCCUUGGUGAAAGAAUUCCCAAGGAAAUUUGGGAAUCUUUUAGGAUUCACUUCAAUGGAAUGUUUCUUGGGACAUGUGUCUUCAGGCACUGGAAGCCACUCACGGACAAGAAGGCACGGAUGACCCCUUGCUCAGCAAUGUGGGAUUAGCCUCUUUGGGCAGGGCAAUCUCUCUGCCCCCAGUGGCUUAGACAGCUGGCUCUGAGACAUAGCAGAAGGUCUCACAAAUGUUAGGAAAAGGGGGUUGAGCAUUAUUCCUCCAUGUGGAAUUAUUUUUGUAUUUAUCCAGAAAGUGACUCUUUUUUGGUCUUUGAAAUCAUCUGUGAUAUAAUUAGAAGAUGUCAGAGCUUCAAUGUCCAUGUCACUAACCUCCCCACUCGGUACCUGGGAAGUCUGAGGUCCACAGAAGGAAAUGUCUUAAUGAGGGUCACCCAACAAGUUAGGGCAGGAGGGAUGCCCCCGCCCAGCCUGCCUCCCAUACCCUGCCACCUCCAACCUUGCUGUCUGUCAUCUUCCUUUACCAAGGAAGGGCUCCUCUGAAGCCAUGAUGAUUUGGGGCCCUUUGGCAGCAGACAGCAAACUAUUCAUACCUUUGGUUUUUCUAAACUGGUGGAGACCUGAGACCAGGGUUCUGGCUUUUCCAUGAGGACCAUAAUAUGCUCCUAUUCCUGCUGUUCCCUUCUUUUCUAUUGCAAGGAGCAUGAAAUGGAGCACUCCUCUUCUGGGGGCCAUGGGAAAGGAGCCAUUCCCAGAUGCCGUGAUGCGUGACUUCAGCAAUCUGGCUGAAGUGACUAGAAUGGGCCCUGUUGUUCUCGGCAGAGCAGGCUUGGGUCAGGCAGGGCGGCUGUUAAGAGGACACGGCCGGCAUUGAUUCUGGGAGUAUCGUUUCCUCCCUCCCCCGGCCUCCCAAGCACACCUGUGUGGGAGGUACCAGGCAGAGGGCCCAGUGUGCUCCUUUCAGUCCCCUUGCCUGUCCCACCUCACUGAACUCGCACAAAGAGCUUCACUUUGAACCGAAAGGUCAGGGGUGACCAGACUUUUCGCUAAGCUGGUUCAAAGGGAGGAGCCUGGGCCGGGUGAGAUAGAUUUUGGCCCUUUUCUCAGUGUGGGAGAGUAUCUGUUUGUUCCUGGGCACAACUACAGUCAUAUUCAGAGGAGAAAUUGCGGAGAUGGCAUAGAAGCCGAAGCUGGCCACCGCCAAAGCCCGUCUAAGUUCUCUAUGUGUGCUACAGAGGGCUUGCACAAAGACAUCUCUCCAAGCGACAUUAUAGCCUGAAAAGGAAAUCUCACAUCUUUUCCUUUAUUAAGUUCCUGUCUGUAGGUUUACCUAGACAGAUUCCCAUAGUAAACUUCUAUAUGAGUAAAAGGAAACAAAAAUAACGGUGGCUUAAAUAAAAUCGAAGUUUAAUAAACUAGAAGUUUAAUUCAGGCGGGCAUGGUGGCUCACGCCUGUAAUCCCAACACUUUGGGAUCACUUGAGGUCAGGAGUUUGAGACCAACCUGGCCAACAUGGUGAAAUGCUGUCCCUACUAAAAAUACAAAAAUUAGCCAGGUGUGGUGGUGCAUGCCUGCAAUCCCAACUACUGGGGAGGCUGAGGCAGGAGAAUUGCUGGAACCCAGGAGGUAGAGGUUGCAGUGAGCCGAGCUCCCGCCACUACACUCUAGCCUGGUGACAGAGCAAGACUCUGUCUUAAUAAAAUAAAAUAAAAUAAUAAAAUAAAAUAGCUUAAUUCUGUCUCAAUAAAAUGAGUCCAUCAUCUAGGGCUAUUUUGGUUCUACACAGGGUCAGGGCCUAAGUUUUCUCUCUGCUUGCAUUGGCAUCCUCAGUGCAUGCAUGGCUCCUACUAUAUGGCCCAAGAUAGCUGCUGAAAAUCCAGCCAUCACAUCUUCUUUCCAGCUAGCAGGAAGGAGAAGGGAGAGAAGAAAGUCUCUCUGUCCUUCCUUUAAGGGAAUUUCCUGGAAUUCAAACACUACACUUCUGCUAUAUUGGCCAGAGCUGAAUUUCAAGGCCACAACUAAUGCAAGGGAGACUGAGGAAUGUAAUCUUUAUUCUAGGUAGCCAUGUGCCCAGAUAAAAACCAGGGAUUCUGUUACCGAGGAAGGAGAAGAAAAUGAAUACUGGGGACAAUUAGCUAUCUUUGCUACAUCUUCCUCCUAGAUAGAUAAGAGGGCUUAUAACAUGUGGGCAUCUAUAUUUAUGUUUCCAAUAUUAUUAUCCGGGACUGGAUUAGAAGCAUAGACUGAUAAUGUAAAGGUUAGAAAUCAGCCAGUCCACACCCUCAUUUUAAAGGUUAGAAAACUGAGAUCCAGAGAGAUUAAACAGAUCAUCUGAGAUCACACAGCGAGUUGGUGGAAUCUAAUUCCCAGCUCAUGUUCAGUGGGAGUAUUUUUGUUCUGCUCUGUUUCUUAACUUAAGAGAAAAGCUUCAUUCUGGAGGGGAAGGAGUUUUGAGUGCCAAGGAUGAAAUUCCACCCAUCACUCGGUCUCUGAGCUGCAGGACACAGGCAGGACAACGGUAGGAUUUUCAUGCCCCGAUCUGCCUGGCCUUGAGUUGUGGCAGCUGGGGAAGCCACUGGUGAGGACGCUGCACUGGAGUGUGGGCUGGCUGAGUGUGCCCAUUCUGUCACUGCCUGUCCCGUGUCUGUGUGUGUGCAUGUGGCUCUGUUUAUCUCCAUGUCGGCCCUGUAUACUGAUUCCAGCCUGCCAAGGCUGCAUGUCUGACUCUGUGUGCUUCUCUUUCAGGGAGCACACUGCCAGGAUGGGAGCUGCUGGGAGGCAGGACUUCCUCUUCAAGGCCAUGCUGACCAUCAGCUGGCUCACUCUGACCUGCUUCCCUGGGGCCACAUCCACAGUGGCUGCUGGGUGCCCUGACCAGAGCCCUGAGUUGCAACCCUGGAACCCUGGCCAUGACCAAGACCACCAUGUGCAUAUCGGCCAGGGCAAGACACUGCUGCUCACCUCUUCUGCCACGGUCUAUUCCAUCCACAUCUCAGAGGGAGGCAAGCUGGUCAUUAAAGACCACGACGAGCCGAUUGUUUUGCGAACCCGGCACAUCCUGAUUGACAACGGAGGAGAGCUGCAUGCUGGGAGUGCCCUCUGCCCUUUCCAGGGCAAUUUCACCAUCAUUUUGUAUGGAAGGGCUGAUGAAGGUAUUCAGCCGGAUCCUUACUAUGGUCUGAAGUACAUUGGGGUUGGUAAAGGAGGCGCUCUUGAGUUGCAUGGACAGAAAAAGCUCUCCUGGACAUUUCUGAACAAGACCCUUCACCCAGGUGGCAUGGCAGAAGGAGGCUAUUUUUUUGAAAGGAGCUGGGGCCACCGUGGAGUUAUUGUUCAUGUCAUCGACCCCAAAUCAGGCACAGUCAUCCAUUCUGACCGGUUUGACACCUAUAGAUCCAAGAAAGAGAGUGAACGUCUGGUCCAGUAUUUGAACGCGGUGCCCGAUGGCAGGAUCCUUUCUGUUGCAGUGAAUGAUGAAGGUUCUCGAAAUCUGGAUGACAUGGCCAGGAAGGCGAUGACCAAAUUGGGAAGCAAACACUUCCUGCACCUUGGAUUUAGACACCCUUGGAGUUUUCUAACUGUGAAAGGAAAUCCAUCAUCUUCAGUGGAAGACCAUAUUGAAUAUCAUGGACAUCGAGGCUCUGCUGCUGCCCGGGUAUUCAAAUUGUUCCAGACAGAGCAUGGCGAAUAUUUCAAUGUUUCUUUGUCCAGUGAGUGGGUUCAAGACGUGGAGUGGACGGAGUGGUUCGAUCAUGAUAAAGUAUCUCAGACUAAAGGUGGGGAGAAAAUUUCAGACCUCUGGAAAGCUCACCCAGGAAAAAUAUGCAAUCGUCCCAUUGAUAUACAGGCCACUACAAUGGAUGGAGUUAACCUCAGCACCGAGGUUGUCUACAAAAAAGGCCAGGAUUAUAGGUUUGCUUGCUACGACCGGGGCAGAGCCUGCCGGAGCUACCGUGUACGGUUCCUCUGUGGGAAGCCUGUGAGGCCCAAACUCACAGUCACCAUUGACACCAAUGUGAACAGCACCAUUCUGAACUUGGAGGAUAAUGUACAGUCAUGGAAACCUGGAGAUACCCUGGUCAUUGCCAGUACUGAUUACUCCAUGUACCAGGCAGAAGAGUUCCAGGUGCUUCCCUGCAGAUCCUGCGCCCCCAACCAGGUCAAAGUGGCAGGGAAACCAAUGUACCUGCACAUCGGGGAGGAGAUAGACGGCGUGGACAUGCGGGCGGAGGUUGGGCUUCUGAGCCGGAACAUCAUAGUGAUGGGGGAGAUGGAGGACAAAUGCUACCCCUACAGAAACCACAUCUGCAAUUUCUUUGACUUCGAUACCUUUGGGGGCCACAUCAAGUUUGCUCUGGGAUUUAAGGCAGCACACUUGGAGGGCACGGAGCUGAAGCAUAUGGGACAGCAGCUGGUGGGUCAGUACCCGAUUCACUUCCACCUGGCCGGUGAUGUAGACGAAAGGGGAGGUUAUGACCCACCCACAUACAUCAGGGACCUCUCCAUCCAUCAUACAUUCUCUCGCUGCGUCACAGUCCAUGGCUCCAAUGGCUUGUUGAUCAAGGACGUUGUGGGCUAUAACUCUUUGGGCCACUGCUUCUUCACGGAAGAUGGGCCGGAGGAACGCAACACUUUUGACCACUGUCUUGGCCUCCUUGUCAAGUCUGGAACCCUCCUCCCCUCGGACCGUGACAGCAAGAUGUGCAAGAUGAUCACAGAGGACUCCUACCCGGGGUACAUCCCCAAGCCCAGGCAAGACUGCAAUGCUGUGUCCACCUUCUGGAUGGCCAAUCCCAACAACAACCUCAUCAACUGUGCCGCUGCAGGAUCUGAGGAAACUGGAUUUUGGUUUAUUUUUCACCACGUACCAACGGGCCCCUCCGUGGGAAUGUACUCCCCAGGUUAUUCAGAGCACAUUCCACUGGGAAAAUUCUAUAACAACCGAGCACAUUCCAACUACCGGGCUGGCAUGAUCAUAGACAACGGAGUCAAAACCACCGAGGCCUCUGCCAAGGACAAGCGGCCGUUCCUCUCAAUCAUCUCUGCCAGAUACAGCCCUCACCAGGACGCCGACCCGCUGAAGCCCCGGGAGCCGGCCAUCAUCAGACACUUCAUUGCCUACAAGAACCAGGACCACGGGGCCUGGCUGCGCGGCGGGGAUGUGUGGCUGGACAGCUGCCGGUUUGCUGACAAUGGCAUUGGCCUGACCCUGGCCAGUGGUGGAACCUUCCCGUAUGACGACGGCUCCAAGCAAGAGAUAAAGAACAGCUUGUUUGUUGGCGAGAGUGGCAACGUGGGGACGGAAAUGAUGGACAAUAGGAUCUGGGGCCCUGGCGGCUUGGACCAUAGCGGAAGGACCCUCCCUAUAGGCCAGAAUUUUCCAAUUAGAGGAAUUCAGUUAUAUGAUGGCCCCAUCAACAUCCAAAACUGCACUUUCCGAAAGUUUGUGGCCCUGGAGGGCCGGCACACCAGCGCCCUGGCCUUCCGCCUGAAUAAUGCCUGGCAGAGCUGCCCCCAUAACAACGUGACCGGCAUUGCCUUUGAGGACGUUCCGAUUACUUCCAGAGUGUUCUUCGGAGAGCCUGGGCCCUGGUUCAACCAGCUGGACAUGGAUGGGGAUAAGACAUCUGUGUUCCAUGACGUCGACGGCUCCGUGUCCGAGUACCCUGGCUCCUACCUCACGAAGAAUGACAACUGGCUGGUCCGGCACCCAGACUGCAUCAAUGUUCCCGACUGGAGAGGGGCCAUUUGCAGUGGGUGCUAUGCACAGAUGUACAUUCAAGCCUACAAGACCAGUAACCUGCGAAUGAAGAUCAUCAAGAAUGACUUCCCCAGCCACCCUCUUUACCUGGAGGGGGCGCUCACCAGGAGCACCCAUUACCAGCAAUACCAACCGGUUGUCACCCUGCAGAAGGGCUACACCAUCCACUGGGACCAGACGGCCCCCGCCGAACUCGCCAUCUGGCUCAUCAACUUCAACAAGGGCGACUGGAUCCGAGUGGGGCUCUGCUACCCGCGAGGCACCACAUUCUCCAUCCUCUCGGAUGUUCACAAUCGCCUGCUGAAGCAAACGUCCAAGACGGGCGUCUUCGUGAGGACCUUGCAGAUGGACAAAGUGGAGCAGAGCUACCCUGGCAGGAGCCACUACUACUGGGACGAGGACUCAGGGCUGUUGUUCCUGAAGCUGAAAGCUCAGAACGAGAGAGAGAAGUUUGCUUUCUGCUCCAUGAAAGGCUGUGAGAGGAUAAAGAUUAAAGCUCUGAUUCCAAAGAACGCAGGCGUCAGUGACUGCACAGCCACAGCUUACCCCAAGUUCACCGAGAGGGCUGUCGUAGACGUGCCGAUGCCCAAGAAGCUCUUUGGUUCUCAGCUGAAAACAAAGGACCAUUUCUUGGAGGUGAAGAUGGAGAGUUCCAAGCAGCACUUCUUCCACCUCUGGAACGACUUCGCUUACAUUGAAGUGGAUGGGAAGAAGUACCCCAGUUCGGAGGAUGGCAUCCAGGUGGUGGUGAUUGACGGGAACCAAGGGCGCGUGGUGAGCCACACGAGCUUCAGGAACUCCAUUCUGCAAGGCAUACCAUGGCAGCUUUUCAACUAUGUGGCGACCAUCCCUGACAAUUCCAUAGUGCUUAUGGCAUCAAAGGGAAGAUACGUCUCCAGAGGCCCAUGGACCAGAGUGCUGGAAAAGCUUGGGGCAGACAGGGGUCUCAAGUUGAAAGAGCAAAUGGCAUUCGUUGGCUUCAAAGGCAGCUUCCGGCCCAUCUGGGUGACACUGGACACUGAGGAUCACAAAGCCAAAAUCUUCCAAGUUGUGCCCAUCCCUGUGGUGAAGAAGAAGAAGUUGUGAGGACAGCUGCCGCCCGGUGCCACCUCGUGGUAGACUAUGACGGUGACUCUUGGCAGCAGACCAGUGGGGGAUGGCUGGGUCCCCCAGCCCCUGCCAGCAGCUGCCUGGGAAGGCCGUGUUUCAGCCCUGAUGGGCCAAGGGAAGGCUAUCAGAGACCCUGGUGCUGCCACCUGCCCCUACUCAAGUGUCUACCUGGAGCCCCUGGGGCGGUGCUGGCCAAUGCUGGAAACAUUCACUUUCCUGCAGCCUCUUGGGUGCUUCUCUCCUAUCUGUGCCUCUUCAGUGGGGGUUUGGGGACCAUAUCAGGAGACCUGGGUUGUGCUGACAGCAAAGAUCCACUUUGGCAGGAGCCCUGACCCAGCUAGGAGGUAGUCUGGAGGGCUGGUCAUUCACAGAUCCCCAUGGUCUUCAGCAGACAAGUGAGGGUGGUAAAUGUAGGAGAAAGAGCCUUGGCCUUAAGGAAAUCUUUACUCCUGUAAGCAAGAGCCAACCUCACAGGAUUAGGAGCUGGGGUAGAACUGGCUAUCCUUGGGGAAGAGGCAAGCCCUGCCUCUGGCCGUGUCCACCUUUCAGGAGACUUUGAGUGGCAGGUUUGGACUUGGACUAGAUGACUCUCAAAGGCCCUUUUAGUUCUGAGAUUCCAGAAAUCUGCUGCAUUUCACAUGGUACCUGGAACCCAACAGUUCAUGGAUAUCCACUGAUAUCCAUGAUGCUGGGUGCCCCAGCGCACACGGGAUGGAGAGGUGAGAACUAAUGCCUAGCUUGAGGGGUCUGCAGUCCAGUAGGGCAGGCAGUCAGGUCCAUGUGCACUGCAAUGCCAGGUGGAGAAAUCACAGAGAGGUAAAAUGGAGGCCAGUGCCAUUUCAGAGGGGAGGCUCAGGAAGGCUUCUUGCUUACAGGAAUGAAGGCUGGGGGCAUUUUGCUGGGGGGAGAUGAGGCAGCCUCUGGAAUGGCUCAGGGAUUCAGCCCUCCCUGCCGCUGCCUGCUGAAGCUGGUGACUACGGGGUCGCCCUUUGCUCACGUCUCUCUGGCCCACUCAUGAUGGAGAAGUGUGGUCAGAGGGGAGCAAUGGGCUUUGCUGCUUAUGAGCACAGAGGAAUUCAGUCCCCAGGCAGCCCUGCCUCUGACUCCAAGAGGGUGAAGUCCACAGAAGUGAGCUCCUGCCUUAGGGCCUCAUUUGCUCUUCAUCCAGGGAACUGAGCACAGGGGGCCUCCAGGAGACCCUAGAUGUGCUCGUACUCCCUCGGCCUGGGAUUUCAGAGCUGGAAAUAUAGAAAAUAUCUAGCCCAAAGCCUUCAUUUUAACAGAUGGGGAAAGUGAGCCCCCAAGAUGGGAAAGAACCACACAGCUAAGGGAGGGCCUGGGGAGCCCCACCCUAGCCCUUGCUGCCACACCACAUUGCCUCAACAACCGGCCCCAGAGUGCCCAGGCACUCCUGAGGUAGCUUCUGGAAAUGGGGACAAGUCCCCUCGAAGGAAAGGAAAUGACUAGAGUAGAAUGACAGCUAGCAGAUCUCUUCCCUCCUGCUCCCAGCGCACACAAACCCGCCCUCCCCUUGGUGUUGGCGGUCCCUGUGGCCUUCACUUUGUUCACUACCUGUCAGCCCAGCCUGGGUGCACAGUAGCUGCAACUCCCCAUUGGUGCUACCUGGCUCUCCUGUCUCUGCAGCUCUACAGGUGAGGCCCAGCAGAGGGAGUAGGGCUCGCCAUGUUUCUGGUGAGCCAAUUUGGCUGAUCUUGGGUGUCUGAACAGCUAUUGGGUCCACCCCAGUCCCUUUCAGCUGCUGCUUAAUGCCCUGCUCUCUCCCUGGCCCACCUUAUAGAGAGCCCAAAGAGCUCCUGUAAGAGGGAGAACUCUAUCUGUGGUUUAUAAUCUUGCACGAGGCACCAGAGUCUCCCUGGGUCUUGUGAUGAACUACAUUUAUCCCCUUUCCUGCCCCAACCACAAACUCUUUCCUUCAAAGAGGGCCUGCCUGGCUCCCUCCACCCAACUGCACCCAUGAGACUCGGUCCAAGAGUCCAUUCCCCAGGUGGGAGCCAACUGUCAGGGAGGUCUUUCCCACCAAACAUCUUUCAGCUGCUGGGAGGUGACCAUAGGGCUCUGCUUUUAAAGAUAUGGCUGCUUCAAAGGCCAGAGUCACAGGAAGGACUUCUUCCAGGGAGAUUAGUGGUGAUGGAGAGGAGAGUUAAAAUGACCUCAUGUCCUUCUUGUCCACGGUUUUGUUGAGUUUUCACUCUUCUAAUGCAAGGGUCUCACACUGUGAACCACUUAGGAUGUGAUCACUUUCAGGUGGCCAGGAAUGUUGAAUGUCUUUGGCUCAGUUCAUUUAAAAAAGAUAUCUAUUUGAAAGUUCUCAGAGUUGUACAUAUGUUUCACAGUACAGGAUCUGUACAUAAAAGUUUCUUUCCUAAACCAUUCACCAAGAGCCAAUAUCUAGGCAUUUUCUUGGUAGCACAAAUUUUCUUAUUGCUUAGAAAAUUGUCCUCCUUGUUAUUUCUGUUUGUAAGACUUAAGUGAGUUAGGUCUUUAAGGAAAGCAACGCUCCUCUGAAAUGCUUGUCUUUUUUCUGUUGCCGAAAUAGCUGGUCCUUUUUCGGGAGUUAGAUGUAUAGAGUGUUUGUAUGUAAACAUUUCUUGUAGGCAUCACCAUGAACAAAGAUAUAUUUUCUAUUUAUUUAUUAUAUGUGCACUUCAAGAAGUCACUGUCAGAGAAAUAAAGAAUUGUCUUAAAUGUCAUGAUUGGAGAUGUCCUUUGCAUUGCUUGGAAGGGGUGUACCUAGAGCCAAGGAAAUUGGCUCUGGUUUGGAAAAAUUUUGCUGUUAUUAUAGUAAACAUACAAAGGAUGUCA